ACCAGUCACCCAGCCACGCUCUAGGGUGGUAGCCAAGAAGACGGACCCCGAGCGGGAGGCAGAGAGACAAGAGGUGGAUGAAGCAGAGCAAGCGUGAGCAUGGUGAAGAGAAGACGGAGCCCCGCGCUGGGAGAGGAACGCUUCAGUCCGAGUUCCAUUCUGCACCCAAGGCUCCCCUUGGUCCUCCUGGGAACCAGGGUGCCCCUUAGUGGUGGUGGCCCAGGAGAACCCGACCAAGGCAGGAGCGCCCCCUCCUGGAAGAGCCUCGCUUCAACGCAUCAUCAUUCCCGGCCGGCAGCAGGGGCGACGCCAGCAAGGCCUGCGACUCAGAGCCAGCUUGGCCCGUUCGCCCCGCCCCUUCCCGGUGUCCGCCCCGCCCCUUUCCCGGUGUCCGCCCCGCCUCCUUCCCGGUGUCCGCCCCGCCCCCUUCCCUGUGUCCGCCCCGCCCCCUUCCCUGUGUCCGCCCUGCCCGCUUCACUGUGGUCCUGCCUCUGGGUGGUGCCGGGGCGGGGGGUGGGAGCCCGGGGCCCGCGCAGGCGGAGAUGUCGCCCAAUGGGAAGGGUCGGUCGGGAAGGGGGUGGGCGCAGGCGGGUGGGCGGGAAGAACGCUGGAGGUUGAUUGGCGGUCUUGCCGGCCAGUGAAGCCAGGGCAUGGGCGGGGCGCGGCUCGGAGCGCGAAACAUGGCGGGGCAGGACGCUGGCUGCGGCCGUGGCGGCGACGACUACUCAGAGGACGAGGGCGACAGCAGCGUGUCCAGGGCGGCUGUGGAGGUGUUCGGGAAGCUGAAGGACCUAAACUGCCCCUUCCUCGAGGGUCUGUAUAUCACAGAGCCAAAGACAAUUCAGGAACUGCUGUGCAGCCCCUCAGAGUACCGCUUGGAGAUCCUAGAGUGGAUGUGUACCCGGGUCUGGCCCUCACUGCAGGACAGGUUCAGCUCACUGAAAGGGGUCCCAACAGAGGUGAAGAUCCAAGAAAUGACGAAGCUGGGCCACGAGCUGAUGCUGUGUGCGCCAGAUGACCAGGAGCUCCUCAAGGGCUGUGCCUGCGCCCAGAAGCAGCUACACUUCAUGGACCAGUUGCUCGAUACCAUCCGGAGCCUGACCAUUGGGUGCUCCAGUUGCUCGAGCCUGAUGGAGCACUUCGAGGACACCAGGGAGAAGAACGAGGCCUUGCUGGGGGAGCUCUUCUCUAGCCCCCACCUGCAGAUGCUCCUGAAUCCAGAGUGCGACCCGUGGCCCCUGGACAUGCAGCCCCUCCUCAACAAGCAGAGUGAUGACUGGCAGUGGGCCAGUGCCUCUGCCAAGUCCGAGGAGGAGGAGAAGCUGGCGGAGCUUGCCAGGCAGCUGCAGGAGAGUGCUGCCAAGUUGCACGCGCUUAGAACGGAGUACUUUGCACAGCAUGAGCAAGGGGCUGCUGCGGGCGCAGCCGACAUCAGCACCCUAGACCAGAAGCUGCGUCUGGUCACUUCCGACUUCCACCAGCUAAUCUUGGCUUUUCUCCAAGUCUACGACGACGAGCUGGGCGAGUGCUGCCAGCGCCCAGGCCCUGACCUCCACCCGUGCGGCCCCAUCAUCCAGGCCACGCACCAGAAUCUGACUUCCUACAGCCAAAUCCCCAGAGGCCAACCUAAAAAGCCGGCUUUAGUUACGAUGACUACAGUUCCCACGUGCGCAACUCUGCCCUUGGCUCAAGGAUUCCGUGAUGUUCAUUUUGGUUUUCUAAGCGAGAGGCUCCGAGCCUUCCAACCUCUGACUGGCUGGUCCUGUGAGACCCCUCGAUCAGGGAUGCUGCUGCAAGUGGUCAUGGCAGUUGCUGACACCUCUGCGAAGGCCGUGGAGACCGUGAAGAAGCAGCAAGGCGAGCAGAUCUGCUGGGGUGGCAGCAGCUCCGUCAUGAGUCUAGCUACCAAGAUGAAUGAACUAAUGGAGAAAUAGAAAGUCUUCAGUGAUGGCCUACGCCAAAGCACAGGAUGGGGCGGGCAGGAAGCCCUCUCCCAAGAUCGAGUUGGCCGAGGAUGGAUGAUUGUGGCAGCAGAAGCCGUUGCAGCCCCACGUUGUGCUCUAGGCAGGGACCUUUGGCCCCUUUGGGGAGGGAGAGACAGACGGGCGGUUUGACUUGGACACAAAGAAAGCCUUGGUUUCUAA